ACUGUUAAGGGGGCCGCCAUGGCCCGGCUGUGGGGCGCGCUGAGUCUUUGGCCACUGUGGGCGGCCGUGCCGUGGGGCGGGGCGGCAGCCGUCGGUGUCCGGGCUUGCAGCUCCACGGCCGCCCCGGACGGCGUCGAGGGCCCGGCGCUGCGGCGCUCCUAUUGGCGCCACCUGAGGCGUCUGGUGCUGGGUCCUCCCGAACCGCCGUUCUCGCACGUGUGCCAAGUCGGGGACCCGGUGCUGCGCGGCGUGGCGGCCCCGGUGGAGCGGGCGCAGCUAGGCGGGCCCGAGCUGCAGCGGCUGACGCAACGGCUGGUCCAGGUGAUGCGGCGGCGGCGCUGCGUGGGCCUAAGCGCGCCGCAGCUGGGGGUGCCGCGGCAGGUGCUGGCGCUGGAGCUCCCCGAGGCGCUGUGUCGGGAGUGCCCGCCCCGCCAGCGCGCGCUCCGCCAAAUGGAGCCCUUCCCCCUGCGCGUGUUCGUGAACCCCAGCCUGCGAGUGCUUGACAGCCGCCUGGUCACCUUUCCCGAGGGCUGCGAGAGCGUCGCCGGCUUCCUGGCCUGCGUGCCCCGCUUCCAGGCGGUGCAGAUCUCAGGGCUGGACCCCAAUGGAGAACAGGUGGUGUGGCAGGCGAGCGGGUGGGCAGCCCGCAUCAUCCAGCACGAGAUGGACCACCUGCAGGGCUGCCUGUUUAUUGACAAAAUGGACAGCAGGACGUUCACAAACGUCUAUUGGAUGAAGGUGAAUGACUAAAGCUUUGCUACUGGGGCUGAGGAUUCCGGAUACCAAGACGCAAACACUUUCACUUUGAGCUGGGCAAAUCUUACUUGGCAUCAACUUGGAUGGCUCGCAUAUGACAGGAAACUGGAUUGCCAAGGCAUGGCAGACUGAGCUGGAGGAAGAUGUCAGAAAUGUUUGCCCUGAAAUCAGUUACGGACAAAAUGUUGGCUACAACUUGAGGAGAAAAAUCACCCCCAAAGGAGUGGACAUUUCCUAACAAUUCUGUAUGGAGGAAGGUGGGGUAAUUGCAUUCGUCUGCAGUAGACACGAGUUCCUCGGACCUGUAUAAUCUCCCAAAGCCAAGGUUUGGUAAUAAUGUAGUCCCCAAAUACCUGAAAGCUGUCUUUAAAAAUGCAGGUAAGCAUGUGACUGGCCAUUUGUGCCGAGUUCUUAUUUUUACGGAGGGCUUGUGGCCUUAGACGCCAGUUUGCUUAUGGAAAUGAAAGAGAAUAGUCCCUGUUCAAGGAUGUGUUUCAUGACAGCACGAGUGUAAAUGAGUGCCCACACAUUUUAACAGCCUUGGGCAGGAUUUUGCUGCUGAGAUCCCUAGAGCAGCUGGUUCUUGGCUCAUUCUUGGGGUAGAGGCCGUGGAUCAGGGCUGGGGGCAGGGGUGACAAUUGAGAAGUGCACUGAGCCCUUUCCUGUUAACAAUUGGGCAUAGAAAGCAGGAUUAGUACUUCCUGGUUAUACACUUAUUUUGUAAAAAUAGAAUUAAUAUCACAGCAACCAAUGUGUAGGUUUAAGAAAGUGGCCAGGUGCAGUGGUUCACGCCUGUAAUCCCAGCACUUUGGGAGGGCGGGGCGGGUGGAUCACGAGGUCAGGAGCUCAAGACCAGCCUGGCCAAGAUGGUGAAACCCUGUCUCUACUAAAGAUACAAAAAUUAGCCGGGCGUGGUGGCGAGCACCUGUAAUCCCAGCUACUCGUGAAGCCAAGGCAGAGAAUUACUUGAACCCAGGAGGCGGAGGUUACAGUGAGCUGAGAUCACGCCACUGCACUCCAUCCAGCCUGGGCGACAGAGCGAGACUCAAAAGUAUGAUUCUGGCUGUAGAGUUUUCUUUUUUUCUCUGUCUCAAAAAAAAAAAGUGUCAGCUUUGUCUUGUCAAGAGGUGAAGGAACUUGUUUUAUUCUUUUAUUUUUUUUUUAAGAUAGAGACGGGGGUCUUACUAUGUUGCCCAGGCUGGCCUCAAAUUCCUGGUCUCAGGCAAUCCUCCUGCCUCGGCCUCCCAAAGUGCUGGGAUCAGUUGUGAGCCACACUACCCAGCCAAACUCCAGUUUUAGUUAAACUGUUUCACCUCAUUUUUAUGCUGAGUUUUGUAAAGUAGGUAUUCUUGCUGAACAGAGUCCUGAAAAUCAAACUAUACAAGUAGUAGGAAGUCCAUUAAGCUGUUUAGAGGAAAAAGUGUUAUAAAUGGCAGUUAAAUGAACCCAGGAAAGACCCAUCCUCCUUUGUGGCUUUCUCUGAGGCCCCAUGAGGCCAAGCAGAAGCAAACUGGCUCUAGGUGCAGCCAGACUUUGAAAAGGAAUCCCGGCCAGGCUUGGUGGCUCAUGCCUGUAAUCCCAGCACUUUGGGAGGUCAAGGCAGGCAGAUCACCUGAGGUCAGGAGUUCAAGACCAGCCUGGCCAACAUGGCGAAACACUGUUUCUACUAAAAAUAUGAAAAUUAGCUGGGUGUGCUGGUAGGCGCCUGUAAUCACAGCUACUUGGGAGGCUGAGGCGGGAGAAUCGCUCAAACCUGGGAGGCAGAGGUUGCAGUGGGCUGAGAUCUCGCCACUGUACUCCAGCCUGGGCGACAGACCAAGGCUCUGUCUCAAAAAAAAAAAAAAAAAAAAAAAAAGGGAAUCCCAACCAGAUACUGGUGCAAGGUCAGAGAUGCAGCCAAUGGGGAGAUUUGUAGAAAGCUCAUAGAUGCUAAAAACAUGGGUCUUUAGGAAAAUUAGAAUUCAGCUGAGCCUCCUUUCAUUUGGACAAUGUUCAGAAGCUCUUACAGGGGGCUAUGGCAAUCUUUUGAUGCUUCUUAUAGCUUUCUGAGGUUAACGCUUUUGUGGUGGGCAUCGGUAGCAAUAAAAUGCAAACUUUAUUGCA